CCAAACUUCGGGCGGCGGCUGAGGCGGCGGCCGAGGAGCGGCGGACUCGGGGCGCGGGGAGUCGAGGCAUUUGCGCCUGUGCUUCGGACCGUAGCGCCAGGGCCUGAGCCUUUGAAGCAGGAGGAGGGGAGGAGAGAGUGGGGCUCCUCUAUCGGGACCCCCUCCCCAUGUGGAUCUGCCCAGGCGGCGGCGGCGGCGGCGGCGGCGGCGGAGGAGGCGGCGACCGAGAAGAUGCCCGCCCUGCGCCGCUCUGCUGUGGGCGCUGCUGGCGCUCUGGCUGUGCUGCGCGACCCCCGCGCAUGCAUUGCAGUGUCGAGAUGGCUAUGAACCCUGUGUAAAUGAAGGAAUGUGUGUUACCUACCACAAUGGCACAGGAUACUGCAAAUGUCCAGAAGGCUUCUUGGGGGAAUAUUGUCAACAUCGAGACCCCUGUGAGAAGAACCGCUGCCAGAAUGGUGGGACUUGUGUGGCCCAGGCCAUGCUGGGGAAAGCCACGUGCCGAUGUGCCUCAGGGUUUACAGGAGAGGACUGCCAGUACUCGACAUCUCAUCCAUGCUUUGUGUCUCGACCUUGCCUGAAUGGCGGCACAUGCCAUAUGCUCAGCCGGGAUACCUAUGAGUGCACCUGUCAAGUCGGGUUUACAGGUAAGGAGUGCCAAUGGACCGAUGCCUGCCUGUCUCAUCCCUGUGCAAAUGGAAGUACCUGUACCACUGUGGCCAACCAGUUCUCCUGCAAAUGCCUCACAGGCUUCACAGGGCAGAAGUGUGAGACUGAUGUCAAUGAGUGUGACAUUCCAGGACACUGCCAGCAUGGUGGCACCUGCCUCAACCUGCCUGGUUCCUACCAGUGCCAGUGCCUUCAGGGCUUCACAGGCCAGUACUGUGACAGCCUGUAUGUGCCCUGUGCACCCUCGCCUUGUGUCAAUGGAGGCACCUGUCGGCAGACUGGUGACUUCACUUUUGAGUGCAACUGCCUUCCAGAAACAGUGAGAAGAGGAACAGAGCUCUGGGAAAGAGACAGGGAAGUCUGGAAUGGAAAAGAACACGAUGAGAAUUAGACACUGGAAAAUAUGUAUGUGUGGUUAAUAAAGUGCUUUAAACUGAAUUGACAUUAACAGUAGGUGAUCAACUUUACUAUGUGCUUGUGCUUUUGCUUUUGAUGGAGUAAUUCAUUGUUUUCUUAUCCACCUAAAUGCACCCAGCUGCCCUUGAUUUUCUCUGGGCUACUGGCCUUCACAACCCUCUCCCAUGUACCCUCUCUGACUUUGGGGUAACCCUCCCCUAACUUAAAGCUAGAGAAUUCUGAAACUGAGGAGGGGAUCCUCUGUUAAUCAGUGAGCACUUUUUGAUGAGCUGAUAGAUGAUAUAUGAGAGACUAUGCGUGGCACAAUACUUUGUUACACUCUUCACUGAUACAAGUGUUCUAGAGUGCACACACAACCCAAAGAUAGAAAUAAAAAGAGGAGCAGUGUCGGGGAGCUUGGGGCCUGGUGUUCCAUGGAGAGGGAGAAAGGAACAAGCUUGGCCAAUUCAUUCAACUCCUUAUAAAAAUGAUGAGGAGGCUGAAAACCAAGAAUUUUGAUUGGGAACAGAAUACAAGCAGCUGAAGCAGAUGAAUUACUAAGCAACAAAGAUCCUGUUUUUAUACAAAUAUCCUUAGUACAAAAACAAAAGAAGGAAAACUGUAGGGGGGAGUAAUGUGCUAAGUAAGCAGAAUUGCCUCCAAAAGAAGUUGUUCUAGUUACUCUUUCAGAGUGGGAAUCUUAGAUUCUGGUAUUGUGGAUAUGGUUCACAUAUAAUGGGAUUGUGUGUUUUAUUUUGGAGGAAUUAAAGGUCAUAGUUUGGUCCUCAGUAUAAAAUCAACUGGUAAUUUGUUCAUUUCAUUUGGUAAAAAUGUAUUGACUGCCUGCUAUGUUCUAGGCACCAUGCUGUGUAUUUGGAAUACAGCUAUACAAAGCAUUGUCACAUAAUUGAAAUGAAAAUUUUAUAUUAUUUAAGUCACAAGAACAAGCUAUUUAAUUAUAUUACUUUUAGUUUCUCUUUUAAUAAAGAAUAGAUAAUGCUAUCAUUCUAGAUACUAAAUAAGUAUUUUCUUAACAUAAUAUUACUAUCCACUUUAUCUUGUAGAAGAAAUAACUAAAAUACAUCUGUCUUCACUCCUGUAUUUGUUUGCAUUUUAAGGAUUAAAGACAGAAAUAGAAAUGUAAACAACUUUAUUUUGAAAAUAUUUCAACACUGCAAAUAUCUCUGGGUCUGAUAUUCUAGUAAUCUAAUUGGCUAGUAAUUGAUGUUAGUGUGAUUUAUUGUUGAAGGCUAAAUGUGUUUUUCAGUUUCAAGAAAAUUGCUUUUAAUAAUUGCCUAGAACAAGAGGUUGAUUUGGCAGCAAGAUGUUGACGGGAAGUUAGAGAAGUCAAUAAAGGAAGUUUUUAGCUGAGAGAGAGUGAUUAUUCACUCCCAUAGCCUCUGCAUUGUUAUCCAUUAGCCACGAUAAGAACCUUAGGGAAUUCUGAGAGUGUGUCCAGGAAAGGAUCUGUCAAACUAGAAUAGUAUCUCCUCCUUGAGAAAGGAAAUAACCAAGGAUUCCGCAGCUGAGAGGCUGCCAGGGCUAGUGAAAUAGAGUAAGGAAAUCUUGGCUGUCUCUUAUUCUCUGGUUGUAGUUUAACGCAAGACACUUAUUUACUCACUGAUGGUGUGUGUGUGUGUGGGAGGGGAGAUUAGCAUGAGGGGUGGGAAUGGGGAGAUUUGAUGAAGAGAAAACUAACAUUUUUUUGGUGACUCAGGAACUGUGCCAGGUACUUCCAUGCUUAUUAGCUCAAUUACACAAAAAUCUUGGGACCAGGUAUUAUUUUUCAAGUCUUCCCACAUGAAGUAACUGAAGUUUGGAGAUGUUAAGUGAUUCACCCAAAGUUGUACAGCUAAUAUGUGGUUAGGCUGGGUCCUGAAACCGAGGCAGUUUAUUUUCAAAGCCUUUGCUUUGUGCAUCUUACUGCGCCACAUUGCACUGCACAUCUGCUUCCUGAAAGCACUUUGUAGGUGUGUAAAACUUUUCGUUAAAUGCUUUAAGCUGUUUGGGUUAAAAAUAUAUGUUCAUGUUAUAAGAAAACCAAGACACUCCUAAUUAUAAUCAAAUAGUACUUGUUACAUAUCAAUAUGUGUGUGUGUGUGUGUGUGUGUGUGUGUGGUAUAUAUAUAUAUAUCGCAUUGUGCAGAUGUUUAAAAGUAGUUACAUAGACUAGUUCUUGCUUUUCAGGGUCCCAUAAUCUAAACCAGAUGACUUCAGCUUUGGAUAAAUAUAUAGAAGGAAAUUUAAAGAGAAUUCAAAACAAUAGAUGAUGCAGUGACACUGUGAAUAAAUGUUAUUUAUACAGUUUGUAAGAUUUCAUGCUCAUUGUUCGUAUGUCCCAGGUGGAGUUCAGAAAAUAUUCAGUUCAUUUCCACAAAGGGAAAUAGUGCCUAGAGAUGGUUUUCUUUUAAAAAGUCCUUUUCAUAAUGCAGUGCCCUUCCUUCCAUUGCCCUUCAUUCCAUUGCUUCCCAUGCUUGUCAAGAGACUAAAAUGUUACUUAUAGUAAUAGUCACUAUCUCAAUGUAAAUAGCACCCUUAUUUGAUGAGAAUUAUUAUUUCAGUUCUAAAAAUGGGGAAACAAAGUCAGCAGGAGGCAAAGUAGCUUGUUAAAGUAUUCUGCAACUUUCAAAUGGUUGCUUCCACUGCAUUUCACGUCUUGGCACUUCUAAUUGAGGGUUACUCUAACCACCCUAUUUAAAAUUGUAACUGUCCCCCACCCCCUUAAUUACUAACCCUGGUCUACUUUUUGUUUUCUUUUUCUGUAACUCUUAUCUUCUUACUAUAUAAUUUAUACUAUAUAAUUUACUUCAUUAUGUCUAUUGUUUAUUGUCUGUCUUUUCCAAAUUCUACUGCCUCUUACCCUCUCCAGAAUGAAAACUAGUAUCUUUGUUUUUGUUUACUGAUGUAACCCAAACACCUACAAACAGUGCCCAGUAUAUACUAGGCCCGCAAAUAUAUAUUGGCUGACUGACUGUAUGGUUUAGUAUCAUGUCAUAGUAUUGAGACUGUAACUUUGGUCUUCUCAUUUUCUUCUUUGUAUUGUGCGUCCUAGACUUAGUUUGGCCUCUCCUUUUGUCCUUGUAUACUCUAAUACUGGAUAAGAAUUUUGGAGUCUUUUUCAACUCUGAGUCAGUGAAUGCCACAUAACUUAGUGACUAUAUUUAAAUGGUUAAUUUACAAUUUUUUCCCUGCAAAGGAUACUGUAGUCACUGUGAGUAUUUUAGUAUUACUGUAGGACUCAAGAGGGAAUUAAAACUACAAAAAUGACGCGUCUUGUAUGACACAGAAAGAAAUGUUUCUUCACAGAGGGAGGAGAAAAAUAUCUUCAAGAGAGAACUAAUAGAAUCAAAUCAAUGAACCAUGUCUCAUCUUUUUGGAUAAGUAACUGUUAGUAAUCCAGACACUUCAUGAGCUUUCAUUAUGUAAAGUCUUUAGCAGAAGCUAAAGGAGGGGCACCAACCACAGUAAUUUUAACUUAAGAACAAAAUGGAGCAUGAAAAUAAAUUAUUAAAUCAUUUACUCCCACUAUUUUUGGGUUAGGGCCAAUAAUGGGGAGAGAAAGAGGUAGACUAGUUUUGUGUUUGUGGCUAUUUUAAUAGAGUAGCACAAGUAAUCAAAAAACAGUAGGCUGUUUUGAAUUUACUGGCUGUCCCUUAUGAGUUCACAGUUAGAUUGGACUGUCCUCAAUGUACUUUCUUUUUUUUCUUUCUUUCCCACAUCUCUUUAUUUCUCUGAUUUUGUUUAAACUUCAUAAAGAGCUCUCUGAUCUUUCCUUUCCAAACAAUGAAGGUUUAUCCUUUGUAAACUACCUCUGUACUCCACAGGCUGAUGAUAUGUGAUAUCCCUAUAUCAUUAAAGUAAAGCCUAAGCACAUUCUGUGGCUUUUGUGUCUACUCUGUUGUUGCUGAGCUUAUGAACUAUUAGAAAUAACUCCCUCUUGCAUUUUCACACAUGGGGAAUGUGAUGUUCUCUUGGGUAUUAUGCUAAUCAUAUUUUGGCAGGUUUCUCUGGAGCAGAUGCAGAAAUGAUCAUACCACUUUCCAGGGUGUAUUAUUUUAGCUCCUUUGACUUGGGCCCUAAGUCUGUUUUACCUGAUGUUCCUGAAAGAUGUUCCUGAUGUCCUUCACUGUUCUUUCAUGCUGGAUGUUCUUGCCUAUGCUGCCUCCUCAGCUAUCACCCUCUCUUCCCCUUUUUAAUGUAGAACUCAUUCUUAAUGAUUUGUCAAAGGCACCCUAUUUCACUGAAAUGCCUUCUAUAUUCCCUACCCUCCAAGUGGAUUGUAGACCUUCUAAGGUCUUUUGACAUCUGCAUAUCUCUAGCACAGCACUUACCACGGUGAUUAUUUAUCUGUUCAUCUUUCCAAGUAGACACUCUCAUUUUAACUCCCUACCCUAGUCGCCAGCAUCCCCAGCAUAGUGCCUGUCAUAAAAUGGUGCCACAAUGAAAAUUUGAAAAAUGAAUGAACGUGAUAAACAUAGAUGAGAAUCCUAUAUUCUACAAUUUUUUAAAUGUACUGAAAUUAUUCUUUUUGAAUCCUCCUAUUUAUUUCUGUGACUUCUUUGGUGACAAAGUUAGAAAAAAGUGGAGGUCAGUAGGGAGAUAUGAAGGGACGCAAGUGGAAGCAGUGAGCCUGGGCGGGUGAUGGAGUGGGAGAUACGUGGCACAGGGGUCAGUGAGUUAAUCUGGGCUCAUUCAGAGAAUGGAAGGUGUGUGCCAAGAAAACUGGUUGGAUAGGGAUAGGUCAGGGAUUCCCUCUUGCAUUCUCACACUUGGGGGCAUGUGUCAUUUUCUUUUCUUUUCUUUUUUUUUUUUUUUUUUUUUUUUGAGACGGAGCAUCGCUCUUUCUCCCAGGCUGGAGUGCAAUGGUGCUAUCUCGGCUCACUGCAACCUCCACCUCCCGGGUUCAAGCUAUUCUCAUGUCUCAGCCUUCCAAGUAGCUGGGACUACAGGUGCCUGCCACCAUGCUCAGCUAAUUUUUGUAUUUUUAGUAAAGAUGGGGUUUCACCAUGUUGGUCAGGUUGGCCUCGAACUCCUGAUCUCAGGUGAUCCACCUGCCUCGGCUUCUCAAAGUGCUGGGAUUCCAGGCAUGAGCCACCAUGCCUGGCCGCAUGUGUCAUUUUCUUGGGUGUUAUACUGAUCGUAUAUUUGCAGGUUUGCUUUUGUGACAGACUUCUUCUGGGGGAAAAAAAGUAUCCUUCUAUCUUUUUACUUUUGUCCAGUUCCAGGUAUCCCUGUUUUUUUCUUCACUCUUCCUUCCUUGUUCAUGGGAGUUUUUCUUGAGGACUUCAAGCCCAGCUUCGGAGAAUCCUGGUUGUGUCAUCUCAUCUCCUUUCUGCUCUCUUCUCUACCUAGCCUUUCCACCCUCACACCUCCCGGGGUCUGAAAAUGGAAAGAUAAGGGUGUUUCCCUGAAAGUUGCUCUUCUGUGUGGGGAUGACAGGUUCUAAAGACUCUUUUCUGGUCCCUGCCCUCAUUGCCAUGAUUAAUCAGUUAAGUGGCCCGAGGUUUUGUAACAGCACAGUCUUAAAAUGCUUCUCCCAAGUUUAAUUUCUCUCCAUUUGACCUUUUAAGGAUGUGAAUUGGCUUUAAGCAGUAGACUCCCUUUAGUACGGCGCUGUGAGCCUCUCAGUGAAUCUGCUACAUCCAUUCCACCCACGGGUCUGGAAACUUGUCUGUUUACCUUUCCCUAAAAACCUAAGAUAUAUUUUUAAGAAGUGCCUUGUAACUUUUCAUAUAGCCUUUCCCCUACUUUGGGUAGACUGUUUCUUACAGGAAUUUGGUAGAUCUUUCCAAAGAGAAUUCUGUAUCUCUAUUUUUAAAGCAUAAAUCCUGUCAACUUUGGAGGAGAACUGAUUUGGCUUGAGUUUUCUCAGACAUGGGAACUUUUGACCUAAGUUUGUAUUUUACAUUGUUGAAAGGGAACUCCGGGAUCCCAGAAAACAUAUGGACUGCAAUUGGGUAAAGUUUCUGUUUCAGUACUUAUUCCUACUUACUAGCCGUUUAAUCUUGGUCAAGUCAGCCAUGUGGCUCUCAACUUCCUCAUCUGUAACAUAAAAGGAUUAGAGCAGACAAUCUCUAACAAAUGCUAUAAUACCACUGACAAAUAAUAAUAUUAGCUAAUAUGUGUAAGGCACUGUGUUUAGUGCUUUUUCCCUUAAUACAAUAGCUUUGAGAUAUAAUUUAUAUACCAUACAAUUUACUUCUUAAAAAAGUACACAAUUCAGUAAUUUUAAUAGAUAGGAGUAACCAUCACCACAGUCAAUUCUAGAAUAUUUUUAUACAUCAGAAGAAACCCUUUACCCAUUAUCAAUUACUCUCCAUUCCUCCUAACUCCCUCCCAGCCCUAGGCAACUACUAGUCUACUUUCUGUCUUUAUUUGCCUCUUCUGGACAUUUCAUACAAAUGGAAACAUGCAGCAUGUAGUAAUUUAUGACAGCUUCUUUCACUUAGCAUGAGGUUUUCAAAGUUCAUUGAUGUGGUAGCAUUUAUCAGUACUCUGUGCCUUUUUAUGGCUGAAUAAUAUUUUAUCAUAUGGAUUUACCACAUUUUAUCAUUUUAUUUAUCCAUCAUCAGUUGAUUGACAUUUGAGUUGCUUCUACUUUUUGAGUAUUAUCAAUAAUUCUGUUAUGAACAUUCUUGUAUAAUUUUUUGGUAGACAUUUAUCUUCAUAUUUCUUGGAUAUAUACCUAGGAGCAGAAUUGCUGCGUCAGAUGGUAAUGCUGUUUAACCUUUUCAGGAACUGUCAGACUGUUCUGAAGUGGGUACAUUAUUUUACAUUCCAACCAGCAGUGUAUGAGAAUUCCAGUUUAUCCACAUCCUCAUCAACAGUUGUUAUUGUCUGUCUUUUUUAUUAUAUUCAUCUGUAAUGUGAAGUGUUUAUCUCAUUGUGGUUUUGAUUUACAUUUCCCUGAUGGUUGAUGAUUUUCAACAUCUUUUCAUAUACUUAUUAGUCAUUAUGUAUCUUCUUUGGAGAAUGUCUGUUCAGAUCCUUUACCUACUUUAUAAUUGGUUUAUCUUUUUAAUAUUGAACUGUAAUAGUUUUAAAAAAAUAUAUCCUAAAUACAAGUCUCUUAUCAGAUAAUAUGACUUGCAGAUAUUUUCUGUCAUUCUAUGUACUGUCUUUUCACAUUCUUGAUGAUAUACUUUUCAGCCCAAAUGUUUUUAACUUGAUGGAAUACAAUUUAUUUUUUCUUUUGUUGCUUGUGCUUUCAGUCAUAUUUGUGAAAACUUUGCUUAUCCCACAUUACAAAGAUUUACUACUUCUAAGUGAUUUAUAAUUUUACCACCUACCUUUAGGUCUCUGAUCCAUUUUGAGUUAAUUUUUAUGUGCAAGGAGGGAGUCUAACUUGAUUCUUUUACAUGUGGAUAUUUAGUUGUCCCAGGACCAUUUGUUGAAUUAAGUGCCCAGAACAAGUACAUCUAUAUAUAGAGAAAGUAGAUUAGUGGUUGUCAGAGACUGCAAGAAGUGGGGAAUUGGAGAGUGACUGCCCAUAGGUACAGGCAUGCUUUUUGGCAUUAUGAAAAUAUUCUGGAAUUAGGUAGUGGUGAUGGUUGCAGAACUUUUGGAAUAUGGUAAAAGACACUGAAAUAUAUGCUUAAAAAUGGUGAUUUUUGUGAUAUAUGAAUUAUACUAUGGAACUAAUAAUAACAGUAAUAAAGCAAGGUGUCUUUCCACA